AUGCUUUUCGCUGGUUAUUACAUCUUGCGUUUCUCUGUUGUUAUGUCUGAAACCGUGCCUGCAGCUUCUGCCAGUGCUGGUGUAGCCGCUAUGGAGAAACUUCCAACCAAGAAGCGAGGGAGGAAGCCGGCUGGCUUGAUAAGUGCAAGUCGCAAAGUGCCGAACCUCUCUGUGUCCAAGUUGAUCACCGAGGCCCUUUCAGUGUCACAGGAACGAGUAGGUAUGUCUUUGGUUGCGCUCAAGAAGGCAUUGGCCGCUGCUGGCUACGACGUAGAGAAGAAUAACAGCCGCAUCAAACUGUCCCUCAAGAGCUUAGUGAACAAGGGAAUCCUGGUGCAAACCAGGGGUACUGGUGCUUCCGGUUCCUUUAAGCUUAGUAAGAAGGUGAUUCCUAAAUCUACCAGAAGCAAGGCUAAAAAGUCAGUUUCUGCCAAGACCAAGAAGCUGGUUUUAUCCAGGGACUCCAAGUCACCAAAGACUGCUAAAACCAAUAAGAGAGCCAAGAAGCCGAGAGCGACAACUCCUAAAACUGUUAGGAGCGGGAGAAAGGCUAAAGGAGCCAAGGGUAAGCAACAGCAGAAGAGCCCAGUGAAGGCAAGGGCUUCGAAGUCAAAAUUGACCCAACAUCAUGAAGUUAAUGUUAGAAAGGCCACAUCUAAGAAGUAAAGAGCUUUCCGGGAGGCCAAUUUGGAAAGAACCCAAAGGCUCUUUUAAGAGCCACCCA